AGCGGGAAGCCGAGCUGGGCGAGAAGUAGGGGAGGGCGGUGCUCCGCCGCGGUGGCGGUUGCUAUCGCUUCGCAGAACCUACUCAGGCAGCCAGCUGAGAAGAGUUGAGGGAAAGUGCUGCUGCUGGGUCUGCAGACGCGAUGGAUAACGUGCAGCCGAAAAUAAAACAUCGCCCCUUCUGCUUCAGUGUGAAAGGCCACGUGAAGAUGCUGCGGCUGGCACUAACUGUGACAUCUAUGACCUUUUUUAUCAUCGCACAAGCCCCUGAACCAUAUAUUGUUAUCACUGGAUUUGAAGUCACCGUUAUCUUAUUUUUCAUACUUUUAUAUGUACUCAGACUUGAUCGAUUAAUGAAGUGGUUAUUUUGGCCUUUGCUUGAUCUUACCAACAGUAUCAUUACAGCUGUGUUCCUUUCAGUAGUUGCCAUCUUGGCCAUGCAAGAAAAGAAAAGAAGGCAUUUACUCUAUGUCGGGGGGUCCCUGUGUCUCACAGCGGUAAUCGUGUGUUGCAUCGAUGCGUUUGUGGUCACCACGAAGAUGAGGACCAACUUGAAAAGAUUCCUGGGAGUCGAAGUUGAAAGGAAGCUUUCCCCCGCCAAGGACGCCUACCCCGAAACCGGCCCCGACGCCCCGCAGAGGCCCGCCUGAAGCCAGCCCGGCGCCCUAGCAGAUGCACGUGUCUGUCGAAUCGCUGCCUCCGAGCCCACCCCCGAGCUCGCAUGCUGUCACCCAUUCCAGCCUAAAUGUGACCAUAAAAUUAGGGCUGCUGCUUUUAUCGAGAA